AUGCUCAGUCGGGCAGCUCUCCGGGCCGGCGUGGGAGCCCGCGCUCCAAGGCCCGGUGGGGGGAGGGGCGCUCACGCAACCGCCACUGUCUGGAGCGGGCUCGCCUCUGCGGCAGCCCUCACCGCCCGGGCUUUACUGAAGCGGAGUCUAGCAUGUGCGGCUGCUCCACAGCGGUGUGGGUGGCGGCGGCUCCUCUGCAGCAGCCUCGGCAGUAGGGGUCAGGGUGGCCAAGCCCACCGUGGAGCUCAUCUGAGAGUUGUAAGGUACGGGACUGCCUCGGUCUUUGGGACGCCCCGUCUGGUAGCAUCCCAGAUCCAGCACGUUCCUUCCGGCCCUGCACCCCGGCCCGGUGCCUCACACCCCGCUACCCCAAGCAUCCAGACUCUAAGGCAGCCCCUGCAUCUCAGUCCUGACAUCGCUGUCCCUGGAGCAUCCUCCGCUGGAGCUGGAGCUUGACAGGAUCGGCUUCGCCAUCGCCCGGCGUUUGGCCCAGGACAGGGCCCACGUGGUCGUCAGCAGCCGGAAGCAGCAGAAUGUGGACCAGGCGGUGGCCACGCUGCAGGGGGAGGGGCUGAGCGUGACGGGCACUGUGUGCCAUGUGGGGAAGGCGGAGGACCGGGAGCGGCUGGUGGCCAUGGCUGUGAAGCUUCAUGGAGGUAUCGAUAUCCUAGUCUCCAAUGCUGCUGUCAACCCUUUCUUUGGAAGCCUAAUGGAUGUCACCGAGGAGGUGUGGGACAAGACUCUGGACAUUAAUGUGAAGGCCCCAGCCCUGAUGACAAAGGCAGUGGUGCCAGAAAUGGAGAAACGAGGAGGCGGCUCAGUGGUGAUCGUGUCUUCCAUAGCAGCCUUCAGUCCAUCUCCUGGCUUCAGUCCUUACAAUGUCAGUAAAACAGCCUUGCUGGGCCUCAACAAUACCCUGGCCAUAGAGCUGGCCCCAAGGAACAUUAGGGUGAACUGCCUGCACCUGGACUUAUCAAGACUAGCUUCAGCAGGAUGCUCUGGAUGGACAAGGAAAAAGAGGAAAGCAUGAAAGAAACCCUGCGGAUAAGAAGGUUAGGCGAGCCAGAGGAUUGUGCUGGCAUCGUGUCUUUCCUGUGCUCUGAAGAUGCCAGCUACAUCACUGGGGAAACAGUGGUGGUGGGUGGAGGAACCCCGUCCCGCCUCUGAGGACCGGGAGACAGCCCACAGGCCAGAGUUGGGCUCUAGCUCCUGGUGCUGUUCCUGCAUUCACCCACUGGCCUUUCCCACCUCUGCUCACCUUACUGUUCACCUCAUCAAAUCAGUUCUGCCCUGUGAAAAGAUCCAGCCUUCCCUGCCGUCAAGGUGGCGUCUUACUCGGGAUUCCUGCUGUUGUUGUGGCCUUGGGUAAAGGCCUCCCCUGAGAACACAGGACAGGCCUGCUGACAAGGCUGAGUCUACCUUGGCAAAGACCAAGAUAUUUUUUCCUGGGCCACUGGGGAAUCUGAGGGGUGAUGGGAGAGAAGGAACCUGGAGUGGAAGGAGCAGAGUUGCAAAUUAACAACUUGCAAAUGAGGUGCAAAUAAAAUGCAGAUGAUUGCGCGGCUUUGAAUCCAA